UUCCAGGUGUCUGGAACUGGAUUACAGUUUCUUCUGAUUGAACGCAGCCUUUGAAUACUGCCUGGCCUAUCGCGAAUACAUCCCUGCCUUGGACAAGACGCAGCUGAAUCUCUAAGUGAUGCUACUGCCACUACCACCCCAGAGCUCCAAACCUGUGCCUAAGAAAUCUCAGUCCAGCAAAAUUGUGCCCAGUCAUCAUGACCCAUCUGAAAAGACGGGGGAGAAUUGCCAAACGAAGAUAUCUCCAUCUUCACUUCAGGAGUCUCCAUCUUCACUUCAGGGAGCACUCAAAAAGAGAUCAGCUUUUGAAGAUCUCACUA